CGGAACGAAGAAUGAUUUCUAAGCGCAGUUCCGCAGCCCACUCACCUCGUCGGCUGGGGCCACCUGCUCUGGGAGUUUCGAUUUCCCUUCCCGCGACUGCACCUCCACAGACAUGGGCAACGCCUUACCAGAGCAACACCUGUGUUUGUUGGGCGGGAAUGAGCCUUGCACUGGGCAGGGCUCAGGGCCCAUCGCGUGCAGCGAAGCGCGGGUGAUUUAAACCCAAGCAGCGGGCGCCUAGAACCCGACCGGAUGCUCCUUGACUUUGCCCCCGGUCUCCGGACUCCUCUGAUUGGACGUGGCUGCGUUCGGCCGCCCAAUGGCGAGGCAGCGCGCGGCUUCCCGGAAGUGGCGGCGCGGUCAGGGCUGGCCUUGGCUUCAGCUGCGGUUUUGGGGUCCCGGACUCUGGGAUCGGCGGCGCUAUGAGUUCUUUCGAGGGGCAGAUGGCCGAGUAUCCAACUAUCUCCAUAGACCGCUUCGAUAGGGAGAACCUGAGGGCCCGCGCCUACUUCCUGUCCCACUGCCACAAAGAUCACAUGAAAGGAUUAAGAGCCCCUACCUUGAAAAGAAGGUUGGAGUGCAGCUUGAAGGUUUAUCUAUACUGUUCACCUGUGACUAAGGAGUUGUUGUUAACGAGCCCGAAAUACAGAUUUUGGAAGAAACGAAUUAUAUCUAUUGAAAUCGAGACUCCUACCCAGAUAUCUUUAGUGGAUGAAGCAUCAGGAGAGAAGGAAGAGAUUGUUGUGACUCUCUUACCAGCUGGUCACUGUCCGGGAUCAGUUAUGUUUUUAUUUCAGGGCAAUAAUGGAACUGUCCUGUACACAGGAGACUUCAGAUUGGCGCAAGGAGAAGCUGCUAGAAUGGAGCUUCUGCACUCCGGGGGCAGAGUCAAAGACAUCCAAAGUGUAUAUUUGGAUACUACGUUCUGUGAUCCAAGAUUUUACCAAAUUCCAAGUCGGGAGGAGUGUUUAAGUGGAGUCUUAGAGCUGGUCCGAAGCUGGAUCACUCGGAGCCCGUACCAUGUUGUGUGGCUGAACUGCAAAGCGGCUUAUGGCUAUGAAUAUCUGUUCACCAACCUUAGUGAAGAAUUAGGAGUCCAGGUUCAUGUGAAUAAGCUAGACAUGUUUAGGAACAUGCCUGAGAUCCUUCAUCAUCUCACAACAGACCGCAACACUCAGAUCCAUGCAUGCCGGCAUCCCAAGGCAGAGGAAUAUUUUCAGUGGAGCAAAUUACCCUGUGGAAUUACUUCCAGAAAUAGAAUUCCACUCCACAUAAUCAGCAUUAAGCCAUCCACCAUGUGGUUUGGAGAAAGGAGCAGAAAAACAAAUGUAAUUGUGAGGACUGGAGAGAGUUCAUACAGAGCUUGUUUUUCUUUUCACUCCUCCUACAGUGAGAUUAAAGAUUUCUUGAGCUACCUCUGUCCUGUGAACGCAUAUCCAAAUGUCAUUCCAGUUGGCACAACUAUGGAUAAAGUUGUCGAAAUCUUAAAGCCUUUAUGCCGGUCUUCCCAAAGUACGGAGCCAAAGUAUAAACCACUGGGAAAACUGAAGAGAGCUAGAACAGUUCACCGAGACUCAGGAACAGAGUAGCAUUUAGUAUAUGGUUAAUUUUCCCCACUACUGAGGCAAGGCUCUUCUUGGUUCUUUUACAAAUGCCCAUGGAUCAUGAGGUUUUCCACUCUGGCUGUUGGGACCAGGACAAGACACUGUUCCUGGCACGGUGAGUUCUGGGCACUUUCUUUCCUUUUGUUUGAGUGAUUCGUUGCCUGGCUGCAGGUAGUUUCCUUACAAGCACAUGCUGCUUAGUGCACUGAACACGUGGUGGGGACGCCUCUGCAGCUUUUCAGAGUUUCUGUGCAGCACUCUCCUCUCUGGUCUUCUGCUCUGUAAACUCCAGGUACAUUUAUUUCUUCAAUGUUCCACUUCCACCUCACAUCAAGGAUGUCCAUGGGCUCUAUCCAGAUGUUCCCUCCCUGACUGGAAUCUGUUAUGAAGCAGGGAGUCAGGCAAUCAUAGGACUCAUCUGUGUCUUAUUUCUCAUGUCAUUGUCCUUAAUUGCUCGAUGUCCAUUUUCUUGAGAGAUAGUUUCUGAUUUUUCGUUAUUUCAAGUGGGAGGUUAAAUCUAGUCCGUUACUCCAUCUUACCUGGAAGCAAAAGUCCUUUCUUCCUUUAAUCUUUUGUGCCUUUUAUGCAUCUACCCAAUCCACACUCCUUUUUGAUAAAUGUCUUUUGGGAUCAGGCAUAGUCACUGAUUUGGAAUGCAGAACUGUUCAACUUAGAGAUCAUACAAAAAUAUUUCAUAAAAAGGUAAUUUUGGGCUAGGCAAAGUGGCUCAUGCCUCUAAUUCCAGCAAUUUGGGAGGCCGAGGGGGUGGAUUGCCUGAGUGCAGGAGUUCAAAACCAACCUGGGCAACAAGGGGAAACACUGUCUAAAAAAAAUUAGCUGGGCAUGGGGGUGGAUCUCCUGAGCCUGAGAGGUAGAGGCUGAACUGUGACUGUAUAAAACUCAAAAAACAACUUUGGCAUAGUAGUGAGGGACCUAAAACAUACAUAUGAUCUUUGGCUUAAAAUCUACAUUCUGCAGUCUAGGAUGAUUCCAAAUACAGUCGUUAGAUAUCUUAGUGACCUUAAGCCCUAAGUUCAGUUACAAGUCAUAACACUGAACCUUUAAGAAUGAGGUUGGGUCGUGUGUAUUGGCACACCCUUUUCUCUGGGCCUAGCUUCACACGGGGAACAUGGGAGCUGGAUAAUGGUCUCUAUGGUCCUUUAUAUUAGUGUCUUAAAAAUGCAGUGUUUAGCCACAUCAUUUAAGUGGAUUAUUAUAACACCAGAUUCAGCAGUAGAACAAGAAGUUGCCAUACACAGUAGUCUUGGGUGCAUUUAACUUUCUUCCUAGGUUAGAUACUGUUACAAGAUGGGAAAAUAUUUGUUUUUCUAAGUAAGGCUUUUUUCAUUUUAAGAACAUUUGUUGACACAGCAUGCUUAUUAAUGUUUUGAAUUUUAAGUUCUUGACACGUUGAUUAUUCAGUAUUUUGCUUUAAAGUUGAUUUAACCUGUUGCAACCUUGUGCAUAAAACAUGUCAAUAAGAUGCUCACAGAAGAAAAACCUUAAUAAAAAGCAAUUUAAUUUUCCUAAGUCAGCCAACCCACUGAGCAUCUACUAUUUGCAGAGCACACAGGCUUUGCAAACCUGGCUGAACAGAUAUCAGCUGUAGAACUUAAAAAUCAAAUUAUUUGGUCCUAUCUUCCUCAGGGAUUCAGUAGGUCUGGAAUGAGAUACAGAAACCUGUUUUUUUUUUUUUUCUUUUUUUGAAGUUUUGCAUAUGAUCGUAAUGAUCAGCCAGGCUUACAUAUAGAGCAGAGUGACUGCUCUAUAUUCUCCACUGAUACUCUGGCAUUUAUUAUAAAAAGUUGAAGGAUGGCAGUUAAAUUGUUCAGCAUAUCCCAAGAAUAUCUUUUCCCUUUGAAGAAGAGUGGCCUCCCUAUUCUUUGCAAUUCCAAGAAUUAAAAGUACAGAUAAAUACUACAAAUUGGCUCCCUUUGCCUUGUUUCCUAUAAACCUGUUUUGUUUGUCCCACAGAGGAGGAAGAUGACUAUCUCUUUGAUGAUCCUCUGCCAAUACCUUUAAGGCACAAAGUUCCAUACCCGGAAACUUUUCACCCUGAGGUAUUUUCAAUGACUGCAGUAUCAGAAAAGCAGCCUGAAAAACUGAGACAAACCCCAGGAUGCUGCAGAGCAGAGUGUAUGCAGAGCUCUCGUUUCACAAACUUUGUAGAUUGUGAAGAAUCCAACAGUGAAAGUGAAGAAGAAGUAGGAAUCCCAGCUUCACUGCAAGGAGAUCUGGGCUCUGUACUUCACCUGCAAAAGGCUGAUGGGGAUGUACCCCAGUGGGAAGUAUUCUUUAAAAGAAAUGAUGAAAUCACAGAUGAGAGUUUGGAAAACUUCCCUUCCUCCACAGUGGCAGGGGGAUCUCAGUCACCAAAGCUUUUCAGUGACUCUGAUGGAGAAUCAACUCACAUCUCCUCCCAGAAUUCUUCCCAGUCAACACACAUAACAGAACAAGGAAGUCAAGGCUGGGACAGCCAAUCUGAUACUGUUUUGUUAUCUUCCCAAGAGAGAAACAGUGGGGAUAUUACUUCCUUGGACAAAGCUGACUACAGACCAACAAUCAAAGAGAAUAUUCCUGCCUCUCUCAUGGAACAAAAUGUAAUUUGCCCAAAGGAUACUUACUCUGAUUUGAAAAGCAGAGAUAAAGAUGUGACAAUAGUUCCUAGUACUGGAGAACCAACUACUCUAAGCAGUGAGACACAUAUACCCGAGGAAAAAAGUUUGCUAAAUCUUAGCACAAAUGCAGAUUCCCAGAGCUCUUCUGAUUUUGAAGUUCCCUCAACUCCAGAAGCUGAGUUACCUAAACGAGAGCAUUUACAAUAUUUAUAUGAGAAGCUGGCAACUGGUGAGAGUAUAGCAGUCAAAAAAAGAAAAUGCUCACUCUUAGAUACCUAAGAAUUCAAAGCGUUUCAACCUAGAGCAACCACUAAAAAACCUGCACAGAGAUGACAGUCAAUAUUACAAUAGAGAAAAUACAGUACUUAAAAAUGUUCAAAUAACCUGGUUGGGUGUGGUGGCUCACACUUGUAAUCCCAGCACUUUGAGGUGGGCAAUGGCUUGAGCCCAGGAGUUCGACACCAGCCUGGCCAACACAGUGAAAUGUGUCUCUACUUACAAAAAAAAAAAAAAAAAAAAAAGCCAGGCAUGGUGGUGGGCUACUCUGGAGGCCCUUGAGGAUCACUUGAGCCCAGGAGAUUGAGGCUGCAGUGAGCCAUGACUGUGCCACUGCACCUCUAGUCUGGGUGACAGAGCAAGACCCUGUUUAAAAAAGAAAAAGGCCAGGCACGGUGGCUCAUGCCUGUAAUCCCAGCUACGCAGGAGGCCAAGGCAGGAGAAUCACUUGAACCUGGGAGGUGGUGGUUGCAGUGAGCUGAGAUUGUGUCAUUGCACUCCAGCCUGGGCAACAAGAGCAAAACUCUGUCUCAAAAAAAAAAAAAAAAAAAAAGAAAAAAAAAUGGUAGAACUAAACCCAUACGUAUCAAUGAUUACAUUAAAUGUAAAUGGUCUAAGUGCAUCAAUGACAAGAGACACGGAAAAAACCAACAUAACCCAGUGAUCUGCUGUCUAUAAAGAAAGUCAAUUCAAGUGAUUGAUAGGUUAAAAGGAUGGAAAAACCAUGUAAACAAUUAAAAAUGGAGUGGUUAUAUGGACAGUUUCCUAAUGAUAAAAGGUCUAGUUCACCAAGAAGACAAAAUAAUCCUAAACGUAUAUGCACCUAACAGCUCCAAAAAUUUAUGAAGCUAGAACAGCUGAAAAGAGACAAACUAAUGCACAAUUACAGCUAGGGAUUAAUUUAACAUCCCUCCUUAGUAACAGAACUAGUAUAUACACAUUAAUCAGUAAGAAUAUAGAACUGAAAAUCAUAAGCCGACUGGAUUAAAUUGACAUUUAUAGAACACACCACCCCAAACUAGCAGAAUGUAUCUCCUGAAGUACACAUGGAACAUUCAGCAUGAUCAUAUCUUUGCUCAUAAACACACCUGAUUUAAAUUGACAAACUUGGAUCUAGUAUGAUAAACUGAUGGCUAUAGACAAAAUCAGCACCUUAUUUAUCCCCAAAGAUGUUAAGUCACUUAACCUUGAUGUGAAUACGGUGGCCAAAUUAGAAGCGGACAAUUAGAAUAUAAAAGAAAAUGCUCAAGAAUUAAAUGGUGGCCAGGCACAGUAACUCCUGCCUGCAAUCCCAGUACUUUGGGAGGCUCGCUUGAGCUCAGGGUUUUGAGUCCAGCCUGGGCAACACACAGGGAGACCCUGUCUCCACAAAAUGUUAGCCAGACAUGGUGGUGUGCACCUGUAGUCCUCGCUACUUGGAAGGCUUAGGUGGCAGGAUGGAUUGAGCCCAGGAGGUUGAAACUGCAGUGAGCUGAUUGUGCCCAGCCUGGGCAACAAAGCAAGACCCCAUCUCAAGAAAAAUAAAUUAAAAAAAACUAAAGUAUAUGUGUUAUUCUGUGAGUCAUUCAACAUUCUUGAAGUCCAUCAAUGUGUUAGGCUUUUGUGUUAUGUAUGAGGAUUUUUAACAAGUUUUAACAGAUAUUCAGGAACACUUAGUUAUUGUGACAUUUCAUAGAUUAUGGAAGCAAAAGCAGAGACACCACUUAAAACAAUUUGCAGAUCAGUUAAACUAACACUUGAUAUGCAUUAUCAUGAUGCUGCAUGGCAAUCCGACCAAAAAGUAUUGGAUCCACCAGACUAACCAGGGUAACAAGACUCAGAGUUAGUAUACACAUAACUAUACACAUUUGUAUAUAUUCACUGUUAACUAAAACUUAGUUUUAACAGUGUACCUUAUGAUCGAAAGUGGUUGUUCAAAAAAUGCCUGUAAACAUUCCUCUGAAUAUAUUCCUGUUAUUUUAUAAUCACAUUAAUAUUACAUACUGUUACGUUUGUUUUAUAUGUGAGUCUGGCAUUAUAAAUGCUGGCUGAAUGAAUUGGGCUAAGACAACUACAACAGAUGUGAUCAAGAAACCGAUAGUGAUUACCAGAAAUUAUAUUUGGUGCUUACUCUGAUGAUGCUCUUAAGUUUUUUACAGACUAUAUGAACUCCUUUAAUUUUCACAACCACCCUUUGAGGUAGAUACAUUUCUAAUCCCCAUGUACAAAUGAGACAAAGGCACAGAGGUUAGUUCACAUAGCUAUGAGGCACAGGCAGAAUUCAAACACAGGCAGUUUGGCUUCAGAGACCAUGAUCUUAACUGCUAUGCUCUGAUGUCUCUCCAAAAAAGUAUAAACAUGAGCAGGGUUAAUUGUAGCAGCUACUUGGUUUUUACGUCAAGAAUCAUAAACCACAAGAGGAAACAUGAAGUUUUUGUUUUUUACUUUUCAAGAUGGAGUCUCGCUCUGUCACUCAGGCUGGAAUGCAGUGGCCCUAUCUCAGCUCACUGCAACCUCAGCCUCCAGGGUUCAAGUGAUUUUCCUGCCUCAGCCUCCCAAGUAGCUGGGAUUACAGGUGUGUGCCACACCUGGCUAAUUUUUGUAUUUUUAGUAGAGACAGGGUUUCACCAUAUUGGUCAGACUGGUCUUGAACUCCUGACCUCUGGUGAUCCACUCGCCUCGGCCUCCCAAAGUGCUGGGAUUACAGGCGUCAGCUACCGUGUCCAGCCGAAACAUGAAGUUUCAAAAUGCCAAGAUGUAUCACAGAAGACACUCAGCAGUCAGCCACAUUUAUCUUGGAGAAGAGUUCCAGGACUUAAAUGUUUGAAUAGUAUAAACUAGUUUUUUAAAAAGUCUGCCUGAAGCCGAAGAUUAAAUACUUUAAAAAGUUCACUGGGUGAUCUUGGCAUGUUGACAUUAUCUUAACAGUCUAAGCUUGUUACCUUACACCAACCUGACAGGUUCAUUAGAAGCACAUGAAUACAUAUAAAAGGCAUAAAAGACUGGGUCAAUGAAUAUGAGCUCUGAAUUCUAAAAUUCCUUUGCAUUUCUAGGCAGUACUUACCAUAGUAUGUUUACGUACCUGGUGAGUGACAAUGCUCAAAAAUUUCUGAAGUAUUCAUCCACAUUAUGCUAGCGAAAUGUCAAAUUGUCCUUUAAUAUUCAAAUGCAUGAACCAUCACUCCUUGGCCUUUUGGCCAAGAUCAAGUGUAGUAUCAAAUGCAUGAACCAUGAAAGCUAUCUUAAAAGGAAAGUAACAUUUAAAGGAAUUGAAUAUAAACCUUCGGUUAAUCUUGCUAGCACGUAGUCAAUACAUCAGUAUUUUUCUGCCCCUUUUAUAGUCUUACUGGAAAUGACUGUAAAACAGAAACAAAGCUAAGCCAUGGUAAAUAGAACAUUAAAUGCCCAACCUAAUUUAUUUUGCUAAGAGAAACUGAUGAACUAAAAGAGAAACAACUAUUGUCUACAUUUUAGAUAUGGGGGAAAAAACCCUGAGAUUACUAAUUAUGUAUCACCAUCCUCUUAAUGUAGAUCCUGAAAAUGAUGGUAUCAAUAUAAUACAUACAGUGGAUUCACCUUUUAAACUGGAUCUAUUACCUUUGAUAUUUGUCUUACACUGAAAAAUUCUGACAUCUUCAGGAAACCAAUAUGAUGGAUAAGCUAAAUGUUGACUUAAAAUAGUUAAACCCCUUAAUAACAUCCUUUAGUUUCUAUUAUUUCACUGCUUAAGUUCAGCAUCUGAAUAACAAAGGUAACAUAAGUAGUACUUAAGAUCCCAAAGGCCCAUUACAUUCUAUCAAUAAAGACAAAACAAAACUA